GCAUUCUCGCGCCGGUGGCGAGGUUAGGGCCCGCGUUGCGACGUGGUGCAGCGCAUAUUUUCACAAGUGGGUCUCCCUUGUCCGGGACUAUGGCCACCGACUCGUGGGCCCUGGCGGUGGACGAGCAGGAAGCGGCUGUCAAGUCGAUGACCAAUUUGCAGAUCAAGGAAGAGAAAGUCAAAGCAGAUACCAAUGGUAUUAUCAAAACCAGUACCACUGCCGAGAAAACAGAUGAAGAGGAGAAAGAGGACAGAGCUGCCCAGUCCUUACUCAACAAGCUGAUCAGAAGCAACCUUGUUGAUAACACAAACCAAGUGGAAGUCCUGCAACGGGAUCCAAACUCCCCUCUGUACUCGGUGAAGUCGUUUGAAGAGCUUCGGCUGAAACCACAGCUUCUCCAGGGAGUCUAUGCCAUGGGCUUCAAUCGACCCUCCAAGAUACAAGAGAACGCAUUACCCAUGAUGCUUGCUGAACCGUGAGUAUGCAGAUGAAGCGCAUCUCACCCAGUGUGAUUAGAUCAAUCUUCCCCAAACUGCGUUUUUGUGCCUGAGAACAGAAGGAGCUGUUUGGGGCCACGUGUUUCCUCAGGAAUACAGCUUAGCCCACAGAAUCUGAUUGCCCAGUCUCAGUCUGGCACUGGUAAAACAGCUGCCUUUGUCUUAGCCAUGCUCAGCCGAGUGGAGCCAUCAGACAGAUACCCCCAGUGUCUGUGCCUCUCCCCAACAUAUGAGCUGGCGCUUCAAACAGGAAAAGUGAUUGAGCAGAUGGGCAAAUUUUACCCAGAACUGAAGCUUGCCUAUGCCGUUCGAGGCAAUAAAUUGGAAAGAGGCCAGAAGAUCAGUGAGCAGAUUGUCAUUGGCACCCCUGGGACCGUGCUGGACUGGUGCUCCAAGCUCAAGUUCAUUGAUCCCAAGAAAAUCAAGGUGUUUGUUCUGGAUGAGGCUGAUGUCAUGAUAGCCACUCAGGGCCACCAAGAUCAGAGCAUCCGCAUCCAGAGGAUGCUGCCCAGGAACUGCCAGAUGCUGCUUUUCUCCGCCACCUUUGAAGACUCUGUGUGGAAGUUUGCCCAGAAAGUGGUCCCAGACCCAAAUGUUAUCAAACUGAAGCGUGAGGAAGAGACCCUGGAUACCAUCAAGCAGUACUAUGUCCUGUGCAGCAGCAGAGACGAGAAGUUCCAGGCCUUGUGUAACCUCUACGGGGCCAUCACCAUUGCUCAAGCCAUGAUCUUCUGCCAUACUCGCAAAACAGCUAGUUGGCUGGCAGCAGAGCUCUCAAAAGAAGGCCACCAGGUGGCUCUGCUGAGUGGGGAGAUGAUGGUGGAGCAGAGGGCUGCGGUGAUUGAGCGCUUCCGAGAGGGCAAAGAGAAGGUUUUGGUGACCACCAACGUGUGUGCCCGCGGCAUUGAUGUUGAACAAGUGUCUGUCGUCAUCAACUUUGAUCUUCCCGUGGACAAGGACGGGAAUCCUGACAAUGAGACCUACCUGCACCGGAUCGGGCGCACGGGCCGCUUUGGCAAGAGGGGCCUGGCAGUGAACAUGGUGGACAGCAAGCACAGCAUGAACAUCCUGAACAGAAUCCAGGAGCAUUUUAAUAAGAAGAUAGAAAGAUUGGACACAGAUGAUUUGGACGAGAUUGAGAAAAUAGCCAACUGAGAAGCUCCACCAGCCACUGAUGCCAGCCCUGGCACUGCCCCUGCACAGGAGACAAGUGCAUUUAGGGCACAGGCCCCGACAUCACCCCAAGGACAACGGCAGAAGUAGAGAGAAACUACCUACCUCACUUCAAAUUAUGUUUGGACUUGACAAAAAUAGGUGCAAAUGAUGGGGGGCAAUAGAAGAAAAAAUUUGCAUUUUGGAAAAUUGGGUCCUUUCCCCACUUUUUUAAAGCCACAUUCCCCCAUCUUUAUAAUAAUCUGGUCACAGUGGUAGUCGCUGGCCCCAGGACCCCCUCCUGAUUUUGGCUAGGCAUCGUGGAACCAGCUCCAGCCCCUGAAGAAACGAUAGAUGUGCAGGUUGUGCGGAAGAGGCUGAGUGGAAAAUGGUGUGAGCCCCACCGCUGUGCAUCGAAUGAGGGAAGUGGCAGCAGAGAGGCCAGAGCUGCCCCCUCUCUGUCUCUUCAAUGGACCCUUCACAAGUGUUUCUCCUGCCCUUGGGGCUGUCUUCCUUCUCCUGAAAUCCAGAGACUUUCUUGCUCAUCCCUUCUCCCUUUCACUUCUGUUCUCUGCUGCAGAAAGCAGACUUGCAUAUCCCUGAUGAGCAGCUCGGCUACUUUUGUAAACUUCAGAUUUGGAGAGAAACACGAAAGUCUGAAUCCUGACCCCUUGAGAGAGAGUGAUCUGGCGAGGGCCGAUGAAGGGGCUGGGCCUGGUCUUGCCUUCUCUUCUCUCGGUUGCUCCCUCUGCCUAGGCCCCUGGUACUCAGUCACGGCAGCCAGGAGACCCCAGGUGAGUUUCUGAGCGCAUACGUAGUUGGUUCUUACCCCCAGGUGUCACACGGGGCCGAGAGCUGAGCAAGAAUUUGGAAUGGAAGUUAUGACCAAGGGAAUUAUGCUGUUCAUUUAUAAUAGUGGACAUUAUGGAGAGCUCUGAUUCCUACAUAAUAUGAAUAAGGAUGGAUAGGCCGGGCGUGGUGGCUCAUGCCUAUAAUCCCAGCACGUUGGGAGGCUGAGGCGGGCGGAUCGGUUGAGCUCAGGCGUUCGGGACCAGCCUGGCCAACAUGAUGAAACCCCGUCUCUACCAAAAAUAGAAAAAAAUAUAGCCGGGCCUGGUGGCGCACGCCUGUAGUCCCAGCUACUCGGGAGGCUGAGGUAGGAGGAUCGCUUGAGCCUGGGUAGAGGCUGCUGUGAGCUGAAAUGGCGCCACUGCACUCCAGCCUGGGUAACAGAGCGAGACCCCGACUCAAUAAAUAAAUAAGGAUGGAUAAAUUGUAGCGUAUGCACCAUUCAUUAUGCUAAGACAUUUUAAAGUAAUUAUGAGAAACGCUCUACUAAUGAUUUGUUUUUAUUUGUAUUUUUCUGCUUAUUAGACAAAUAUAUACUCAUUUUAAAAAGG